GACGAUGGACAAGCAUCUGGGGGAGCAAGGCUGGUGACGGGUUUGGGGGUGCAAGGAGGAUGACGGGGCCAAAGCUUUGGCCUUCUUCAAGGCUCACAGCAAGUGGAGCCAAUGCUGGGAAAUGCGGCACCCUAGGUGGGGCAUGAAUUAACGUGGGCAGACAUCUAGUAUUCCAGGAAAGGGAUAAAUAGAAUUUGAGGGAUUGGUGAGAACGGGUCUAUGGAUAGGAUCAAGACAAUAAAAUGAGAGAAGUGGCUCUAUGACCCCAGAUUUCGGGCAAGCAACCCCCAACCAAUAAACUGACUGUGUUCCCAGAGUGCACAUGUGCAGGUUGGCCAUUGGGAAUUUGGAAUACAUCUUUCUAAGGAAAUAACAAAGCAACCCAAUAGGUAACAACCUUUUUUUGCACAAAAGCCAAUUUGAGAAAAUGAGUAUGUAUGUAGCCUGUGUUUUUAUUUUAUAGUUCCAAAAAAAAAGGUUUUUUUUAAACUAAGAAGUAUAAUAUCUGCAGUUGUGCUUAUGAAUGCUGUUAUUAUUUCUCCAUCUUCGCUACAAUUUCAGAAACUACGGCCAGUAUACACUAGAAUAGCAGGCUUUAAAGUGGCCCCUUUGAACAAAUGUUCUCUAGCAAGACACUUUUUAGAACCAGGUCUUCUCGUUCGCAACUGCACCAUCACUGCCAAUGCUGAGUGUGCCUGUCGCAAUGGCUGGCAGUGCAGGGACAAGGAGUGCACCGAGUGUGAUCCUCUUCCAAACCCUUCGCUGACCGCUCGGUCGUCUCAGGCCCUGAGCCCACACCCUCAGCCCACCCACUUACCUUAUGUCAGUGAGAUGCUGGAGGCCAGGACAGCUGGGCACAUGCAGACUCUGGCUGACUUCAGGCAGCUGCCUGCCCGGACUCUCUCUACCCACUGGCCACCCCAAAGAUCCCUGUGCAGCUCCGAUUUUAUUCGCAUCCUUGUGAUCUUCUCUGGAAUGUUCCUUGUUUUCACCCUGGCCGGGGCCCUGUUCCUCCAUCAACGAAGGAAAUAUAGAUCAACUGGCGUGCUCCUGACACCCCUCCCCCAAGCGCACCCGCCUCUACCCAUCUCCUUCUCCCGUCUCCCCCUGCCCCCACUGCUGGCCAAGACUCAUCGGAUCUCCUUCUGCAGACAAAGGAGAAAGUCCUGUGGAGCCUGCAGAGCCUUGUCAUUACAGCUGCCCCAGGGAGGAGGAGGGCAGCACCAUCCCCAUCCAGGAGGAUUACCGAAAACCGGAGCCUGCCUGCUCCCCCUGAGCCAGCACCUGCGGGAGCUGCACUACAGCCCUGGCCUCCACCCCCACCCCGCCGACCAUCCAAGGGAGAGUGAGACCUGGCAGCCACAACUGCAGUCCCAUCCUCUUGUCAGGGCCCUUUCCUGUGUACACGUGACAGAGUGCCUUUUCGAGACUGGCAGGGACGAGGACAAAUAUGGAUGAGGUGGAGAGUGGGAAGCAGGAGCCCAGCCAGCUGCGCCUGCGCUGCAGGAGGGCGGGGGCUCUGGUUGUAAAACACACUUCCUGCUGCGAAAGACCCACAUGCUACAAGACGGGCAAAAUAAAGUGACAGAUGACCACC